GUGGGAGGUGACACCAGGAGGUAACCAGGUGGAAAUCACCCUCAAGUAGCAGAGACAGGUGUGCAAAGGCUCAGAGGGAGCUUCUCCAGGAUCAGCAGAGCUCGAUUGUAGGGUGUGAGGCUGUCACAGAGGCUGGAGAAAUAAGCAGUUCCUUGCUAAGAAGUCUGAAUUUUAACCUGAAGGGACAUGGGAGCUACUGCAGGCUGGGCUGUGACCGUCUACGACAAGCCGGCAUCUUUCUUUAAAGAGGCACCUCUGGACCUGCAGCACCGGCUCUUCAUGAAGCUGGGCAGCACGCACUCUCCGUUCAGGGCCCGCUCAGAACCUGAGGACCCAGACACAGAGCGGUCGGCCUUCACGGAGCGGGAUUCUGGGAGCGGGCUGGUGACGCGUCUCCACGAGCGGCCAGCCCUGCUGGUCAGCAGCACAAGCUGGACAGAGUUUGAACAACUGACUCUUGACGGACAGAACCUUCCUUCUCUCGUCUGUGUGAUAACAGGCAAAGGGCCUCUGAGGGAGUAUUACAGCCGCCUCAUCCACCAGAAGCAUUUCCAGCACAUCCAGGUCUGCAUCCCCUGGCUGGAGGGCCGAGGACUACCCCCGCUUCUAGGGUCGGUGGACCUGGAUGUCUGUCUGGACACGUCCUCCAGUGGCCUGGACCUGCCCAUGAAGGUGGUGGACAUGUUCAGGUGCUGUUUGCCUGCGUGUGCCGUGAACUUCAAGUGUUUACAUGAGCUGGUGAAACAUGAAGAAAACCGCCUGGUCUUUGAGGACUCAGAGGAACUGGCAGCUCAGCUGCAGUAUUUUGCAGAUGCUUUUCUCAAACUUUCCUGAUCCUGAAGGCAAGCUAAACCAGUUCCGGAAGAACCUGCGGGAGUCGCAGCAGCUCUGAUGGGAUGAGAGCUGGGUGCAGACUGUGCUCCCUUUGGUUAUGGACACAUAACUCCUGGGCCAGAGGCUAAAACCCCA